GAAGGAGGAACCCACCGCACCUACAGGGCGGUCGAGUGAGGGAGCUGCUGGCGGGUGGGUCUGGCAACUCUUUGGGAGGCCGACGCGGGCGGACCGGCGGGUGCUGGGAACCGAGCCUCGGCUUGCGGCCGGCAGUUUCCGUGGGUCUGUGAAGAGGUCGGCGGCCCCUGCGGGCGCCAGUCAGCUUUAAGAAAAAGUAGAGAUCACUUCUGACUGUACUGAACAGCAAAAAUUAAGUGACUUGCUGCCCUGCACAUCAUGGCACUGCCAUUCCGUAAGGACUUAGAAAAGUACAAAGACCUUGAUGAAGAUGAGCUCCUUGGGAAUCUGUCAGAAACAGAACUGAAACAACUGGAAACUGUUUUGGAUGAUCUUGACCCCGAGAAUGCCCUUCUGCCUGCAGGGUUCCGGCAGAAGAACCAGACAUCAAAGUCCACCACAGGGCCAUUUGAUAGAGAGCAUCUCCUUUCAUAUCUGGAGAAAGAAGCAUUGGAGCAUAAAGACAGGGAAGACUAUGUGCCCUACACUGGAGAAAAAAAAGGGAAAAUAUUUAUCCCCAAACAGAAACCUGUACAGACUUUUACAGAAGAAAAAGUGUCUCUUGAUCCAGAAUUAGAAGAAGCUUUGACAAGUGCUUCUGAUACAGAAUUGUGUGACCUCGCAGCAAUUCUUGGGAUGCACAAUUUGAUAACGAAUACAAAGUUCUGUAAUAUAAUGGGAAGUAGUAAUGGUGUUGACCAAGAACAUUUUUCAAAUGUGGUCAAAGGUGAAAAGAUUCUUCCGGUAUUUGAUGAGCCACCAAAUCCAACCAAUGUAGAAGAGAGUUUGAAGAGAACUAAAGAAAACGAUGCUCAUCUUGUUGAAGUUAAUUUGAAUAAUAUAAAGAAUAUCCCAAUUCCAACCCUAAAAGAUUUUGCAAAGGCUUUGGAAACCAACACACAUGUGAAAUGUUUCAGUCUUGCAGCCACCCGGAGCAAUGACCCUGUUGCUACUGCUUUUGCAGAAAUGCUGAAAGUGAACAAAACUUUGAAGAGCUUAAAUGUGGAGUCCAACUUUAUCACGGGAGUUGGGAUUCUGGCACUGAUUGAUGCGUUAAGAGAUAAUGAAACCCUGGCAGAGCUCAAGAUUGACAAUCAGAGGCAGCAGUUGGGGACAGCUGUAGAAUUGGAAAUGGCCAAGAUGCUUGAGGAAAAUACAAAUAUCCUUAAAUUUGGAUAUCAGUUUACACAGCAGGGACCACGAACCAGAGCAGCUAAUGCUAUAACAAAAAACAAUGACUUAGUGCGUAAGAGACGAGUUGAAGGAGAUCACCAGUAAGUCUGCAAAGGUGUAAUCUUUGGAAGACUUCAGAAGAUCACCAAGGGCUCAUGUUGGUGACAUCAUGUAAAAUUUUCCUGGGUAGAAGGGAAAAGACUGGAAAAAUUUUUUUAGUGACAUGCAUUUUUUUUUUAGUUGUUAUCAAAUUGUAAAAUCAGUAAUGUGAUAUUUUAUAUUCUGAAACAUUUCUACUUUCUGCUAAAAUCAAUUUUAAUUUAGUUUAAUUGAAUGAUUUAUGAUGAAUCUUGGGCAAAAAAAUACAACUGUAAAAAAUUUCACAGGUCAUUUGUGUAGAAUAAUUUGAACAUUGUGAGGACCAAUCUUUUUUAAAUCAAAAGGGAUGUUGCUGGUAUCAGAAUUGUUAUUGCUUCAUUUAGACAUAAAACACUUAAGUGUUUUCUUCACUCCGUGACCUGGAGAGUUUUCCAUUUUUUAAAAUACAUGAACUUGGCAAGGGUGUGAUUUUUCUUUAUCAAGAGAACAAAAUGCCAGAAUGUUAAAACAGUUAACUCAAAAUCUAGUCAUCUGUGUAGGAGCUAAAGCAGGUCUCCAGGGAGAGAGGGUGGUCGUCUGUGCAUUCCAGGUUACUGCACUUGUCUGAUGUGACGUAGCAACACCCAGGUCUUCUUAAAACAAAGUCAUCAGCUUUGCCAGGUUACAUACUUUAUUUAAAAGUAUAGUGAGGUCGAAGUUCAUUCCAGUGUUUCAUUUUAAUAAUGUGGGCAUUAUUAAAUUUUUGUGGAAGCUAAUAGUAAAAAAUAAAAGCUGUUUUCACCACCUCCCUCCCCACCCCCCAAAAAAGGCGUACAGCCAACUCUUAGUUAUUUAGGGUAAGAGAAAAAAGAAAACUGUUAAACAAUGAAAUCAAAGAUAAUAAAUAUGAUAGAUUUCCAGUAUGAGGCACUUGCAAAACAGUCAUUUAAACUGAUGGUUACUGUAAGUCAGUUGGAAGCUGGCAUGUAUGUAAAUUACUUGGUGUUACACCAUAUCCGAAGAAGUUCCUAUGUGCAGUGCAGAAUUGCAUAAACAGUAUUUAAUCACUGCUACAAAUCUUCCAACCAAGAAGGAAAACUGCUAUUCUUCAUAAAUCUAAUUUUUAGUAUAUGCUUCCUUUCAUCUUAUACUUUUAUCAAUAUUUAUAAAAGUCAUUUCUAUAAUAAAAGCAGUCUUUCUUGCUCAAAGUAUUAAGGUGAACAAUUGAAUAGAGUACUGUGGUCGGGAGACUGAUUUGAGACUGCAGAGCUGAUGCUGGGUAGAGGGUCUGGACUUGUAUUCAUGUUCUGUCUCAGGGCAGCCCCUGGAGCAGGAGAUGGCAGAGGCAUUUACAGCUGCAGAAAACAGGGAGGAAUGGAAUCUGAGGUAGCCCUGGCCUCAAAAUUCAGGCCUGGCUGUAUCAUUUACAGAGAUUUUUCUGGAGGGAAAAGUCUCAUUUCUGAGGAAGGCAAGGUGGCUAAUCAUUAUUAAUUUUUUUUAAACUUUUUGGGCCGGGCGCAGUGGCUCACGCCUGUAAUCCCAGCACUUUUGGGAAGCCAAAGUGGGUGGAUCACUUAAGGUCAGGAGUUCAAGACCAGCCUGGCCAACAUGGUGAAACCCUGUCUCUACUAAAAAUCAAAAAAGUAGCCGGGUGUGGUGGUGCACACCUGUAAUCCCAGCUACUCAGGAGGCUGAGGCAGGAGAAUUGCUUGAACCUGGGAGAUGGAGAUUGCAGUGAGCUGAGAUCGUACCACUGCACUGCAGUCUGGGUGACAAAGCAAGACUCUGUCUCAAAAAACAAACAAACAAACAAACUUUUUGAAAUUGAAUUGCAAUAUGUCUGCUACUUUGGCUUGGGCUGGACAGUUUAUCUAAUAAGCAAGGCAGCUUCUUGUGUGCUAUGGUAAUAAGCCUUCUUAACAGGCUAAGCUUCCCUCAUAAGAACUGUGGUGUUUCUCUUUUUUUUUUUUUGUUUUGGUUUGUUUUGGUUUUUUGGUUUUGUUUUGUUUUGUUUUUUAAAUCAGUAUCCAAUGUUUUAUAGGGGCCAAAGGUUAACUUUGCACUAUUCCCUGUCAGUUAAAGGCCACUGAUAUUUUUCUAAGUUAGCAAGGCUCACUUGCUUGCUUUCUUGCCUCCCUUGCCUCCAUCCCUCUCCCUUCCUACCUUCUCUAUUUACCUAUUUCUCUCCCUCCCUCUCUUCUCCUCUCUUUUUUUUUCCCCGCAUAUGCAGCUUUUUGAUUGUACUUGAUUUUAUAGAGACUGCACAGUUCCAGCAAGAUUGGGAGUCAGGCAUGGAGCAGGCAUCUCAGGCUACCAGAAAGAAUUGGUCACCUAGACUUUCAGUCAGGCAUCCUCGUUUGCAUUGUCCUGUAAGUCAAUUAGUUGAUAAAUAGUUCCCCCUUCAUCCCUUAAGUUUUGUUUUUGUUUUUGUUUUUAAUAUAGGUAAGUGGGACUCUACCUAAAAUUUUGCAUCAUACUUAUGGGUAAUAUCUUUUUCAUAUAUUAUUUAUCAAAGUAUGAAGUUGAGUAUUUUGCUUGUACCAUUUCAAUUCUGCAUUAUAGUAGUUCAUUGUAUAACUGAAAGAAAUGAUUUCUUCAUAAGUGACAUUAAAUAUGAACAUUCAUCCAAUUGAAUUUACAAAAUCUUUCCAAAAUUAUAAGGGAGAAAAAUCGGGUUUACUUCAAUCUUUAAAAAUCUGGCACCUCUUAGUAACUUUCAGUAUUUCUAAAUUGCUCUAAAAUUUUAUAAUAAAUAGAUUAGGGUUUUGCAAUAGUCUUAAUUUUUAAGCCAAAGGUUUUCUGAGACCUUAGGUUUUGUAGUCUAACCAGCUUAUGUGGUUAUUUAAAAGAAUAUUCUUUGUGUUUUUAAAUUGCUAUUUUUAAAAAAGCUUUUUAUUACCCAUUUUAUAAAAUGUUAUACUCAUAUUUGUCUGAAUUUUUCCAGUAUUCCUACAUGAAAUUGUAUGUAUUAAAAACUCAAUAUUAGUGGCAAAUAUUAAUACUAUUAAAAUGGAUUUUGGUGCUAUAUUCUUGUAGCUAAAGCCUAGUAGAAUUCUCAAGAAUAGGUGAAAUACACUUUCAAAGUUGCCUGUCAUUUAAAAGACCAAAUAAGCAUUUUGUAUUAAAUAAAUUAGCAGAUGGUUAGAGACUUCAAGGAGAGUUAGCUUGGUCAUUUAAUUGCGACUUCAUGUUAUUUGAUUGAAAUAACCCACAUCCUUGCUUUGUAUAAGAUAUUCGCUCUGGAGAAGUUACAUGUAAAUAGAAUUCUAUAAAUUGUUUUCCAGUUGACCGAGUAUCUGUUGUGUUUUUGUUUAAAAAGAGGAUUCCAUGACAUAAUAAAAAUUAUUUUAAAAAAUGUUUUGGGCCGGGUGCGGUGGCUCACGCCUGUAAUCCUAGCACUUUGGGAGGCCGAGGUGGGCGGAUCACCUGAGGUCAGGAGUUCGAGACCAGCCUGACCAACAUGGAGAAACCCUGUCUCUACUAAAAAUACAAAAUUAGCCAGGCGUGGUGGCACACACCUGUGAUCUCAGCUACUCGGGAGGCUGAGGCAGGAGAAUCACUAGAACUCGGGAGGCGGAGGUUGCAGUUAGCUGAGGUCGCGCCAUUGCACUCCAGCAUGGGCAACAAGAGUGAAACUCCGUCUCAAAAAAAAAAAAAUUUUUUUUUUUUUAUAAAAUGUUACUCAUAUCAUAUUGUACGUUAUAUUUAACUCUUGCUGUCAUUAAAAUAAGAUGACAACAUUUAUGAAGUUUUAUAAAAUCUUACAUUUUAGGGUCUGUGUUCCCAGGGCUGCCUCACUUUUUCCCUAAAAAACUAGGAACCACUGUUAACCUCCCAGCAGAUGCAAGGAUCAUGCUUUCUCUGGAGUCCUUAGUCACUUCCAUUCUUUGCAAGUUUAGUACUGCCCAAAUUUACUCAUUCUACAGUGUUACUGCACUUUGAACGUAUUGACCCAUGUCACCCAAGAGAAGCAAACAUAUGGAUGCACUAGAGACAACUCGGGUUGCUGCUCUCAGUUAAGGGCUAUGAGUUCUUGGGGUCUAAGUAUCUGUAAAAUUAUCCUCUCCAUCAGCUCUCACUGAUCAUUAAUGUUUCUGGAUAUUUCUUACCCUAAGAUUUGCUUACCAACAAAUCAAAGAAACGCUUCACUAAUUAUUUUUAAAUUGAGAAAAUAGUAUUCAGAGGCAAAGAUUUUUAUAUUCUUUUUUGAGACCAAGUCUCACUCUGUCAUCCAGGCUGGAGUGCAGUGGUGCGAUCUCAGCUCACUGCAGCUUCCACCUCCCAGAUUCAAGUGAUUCUCCUGCCUCAGCCUCCCAAGUAGCUGGGAUUACAGGCGUCCGCCACCACGCCCGGAUAACUUUUUGUAUUUUUAAUAGAGACGGGGUUUCACCAUGUUGGCCGGGCUGUUCUCAAAGUGACCUCAGGUGAUCCACUCGCCUCGGCCUCCCAAAGUGCUGGGAUUACAGGCUUGAGCCACCACACUCAGCCUUAUUCUUAUAUUUUAAUUUGGUCAUUCUUAGAUCUACAGAUUGAACAUCCCUAAUUGAAAACUUUUUGAGUACUAACAUAGUGUUCAAAGGAAAUGCUUAUUGGAGCAUUUAGAAUUUCAGAUUUUCAGAUUAGGGAUGCUGAACUGGUGUAAUGCCCAGUAUUCCAAAAUCCAAAAUAAUUUGAAAUCUGAAACACUUAAUGGUCCCAGCAUGUUGGAUAAGGGAUACUCAACCUGUAUUGAUUUUUCUCCACUAUAAUUCAGUUCUAUAAGUUCUUCCCUAUAAAAAAUGAAUGAAUUAGAAAUUUGAUAAUAAAACAUAUUUUAUUAAUUUUAAACUCUAUCUUGCAGUCUGAUCAUUCAGAAAGGUCAACCUAGAAAAAAGACAUGGCUAAGUAAACUAUUUUAAGCCAUAACUAAGUAUUUUGGAAAGCCUUCAUUAACACAUAAAGAAUUUUGGCCAAGUACUGUGGCUUAUGCCUGUAAUCCUAGCACUUUGGAAAGCCGAGGCCGACGGAUCACUUGAGCUCAGGAGUUUGAGACCAACCUGCGUAACAUGGUGAAACCCCAUAUCUACAAAAAGUACAAAAAUUAGCUGGGUGCGGUGGCGCAUGCCUGUAGUCCCAUCUACUCGGAAGACUGAGGCAGCAGAACCGCUUGAGCCUAGGAGGUGGAGGUUGCAGUAAGAUGAGAUCAUGCUGCUGUACUCUAGCCUGGGCAAUGAGAGUGAAACUCUUAUCUCAAAAAAAAAAAAAAAAAAAGAGCUAUACUCAUAGUACUUUGGGAGACCAAGCAGGGAGGAUUACUUGAGACCAGGAGUUUGAGACUACCAUGGACAACAUAGCAAGACCCCAUCUUUACAAAAAAUUUAAAAAUUAGCCAGACACCUAUAGUACCAGCUACUUAGGAGUCUAAAGUGGGAGAAUUGCUUGAGCCUGGGAGGUUGAAGCAGCAGUGAGCUUUGAUCAUGCCACUGCAUUCCAGCCUGGGUAACAAGAGUGAGACUGUCUCAAAAAACAAAACAAAACAAAAAAAUGGGUUUUUUUGUUGUUGUUUUUGUCUUUUACUUAGGACACCUGCUCUAGAGGCUAGAUAAAAAUAGAUUGUAAUGGCCGGGUGCAGUGGCUCACACUUGUAAUCCCAGCACUGUGGAGGCUGAGGUGGGCGGAUCACUUGAGGUCAGGAGUACGAGACCAGUCUGGCCAACAUGGUGAAACCCCAUCUCUACUAAAAAUACAAAAAAUUAGUUGGGCGUGGUGAUGCGCACCUGUAAUUCUAGCUACUUGGGAGCCUAAGGCAGGAGAAUCACUUGAACCUGGGAGGCAGAAGUUGCAGUGAGCCGAGAUUGUGCCAUUGCACUCCAGCCUGGGUGACAGAGUGAGACUCCAUCUCAAAAAAAUAUAUGUAUUAAGAAAUACCACCAGCAGUGUUUUGCUAACAUAGCUGUAACAAAUUAUUAAGUUCUUUUUUUUUUUUAAGAUGGAGGUUCACUCUUGUCGCCCAGGCUGGAGCGCAAUGGUGCGAUCUCAGCUCACUGCAACCUCCGCCUCCUGGGUUCAGAUGAUUUUCCUGCCUCAGCCUCCUGGGUAGCUGGGACUACAGGUGCCCGCCACCACGCCUGACUAAUUUUUGUAUUUUCAGUAGAGACGGAGUUUCACCAUCUUGGCCAGGCUGGUCUCGAACUCCUGACCUCGUAAUCCACCCGCCUCGGCCUCCCAAAGUGCUGGGAUUACAGGUGUUUGCCACCGCGCCCAGCCCAAAUUAUUACAUUCGUAAGACAGACACCUCUUAGAAUCUAUAUAUAUGAGGUUUUACUCCCUUUUCUACACUCAGUAUGUUUUAAUUGAUGCAAAGCAAUUAAUUGGCCUAAAAUGUUUCAAAUAUUAUAGUCUAUACAUUCAGAAAGUAAGGUUUAAGAAUGAAUUAUUGGUGCUUCUUGGUGGGUGUAUAUAGCAGUUUUUAGAAGUUUAAAUUUCACCUCUACUCAGAAAGAUAAGCUUUUGAUUCAGUGGUUUCAAAUUUUCAGAUCAAUCCAUUUAAGAAUUGUUUUUUCAAAUGUAUAUACACGUAUAACAUAAAAAUUUUUGUAAUUUCAAAUGUCUUUUUUUCAGUUUUUUGGAUGAAUUAUUAUAUUUGGUUUUAGUUACAUUUAAAAGCUUGAAAAUUACCUUUCUAACAAUCAUUUGAAUGUCAUUCAUUGUCACAUGAAAUCAGGUAUUUACGUUUUUUUCUAAUGCUAAAAUAUCCAACAUUGUAAUUGCCCUAUUUUUCCAUUUUUAUAAGUAUAAAAGCAAUGAAUUUUAACACUGGUAUUUAAAUAAUACAAAAUAUUAUCCAAAUUCAUAACAGCACAGUGAAGUUUCUUUUGAAGACUAUGUACUGGAAGCAUUUAGAACUUACCAAUAUAUACUGGGAUAAAUCGUUUCAAUAAAGUUUAUCAAAUAUUCUGUAAA